AGUACCAUCUCCGACAGGGGCUGAGUUGCUGGAGCUGGGCUGGGGCAGGGGAGAAAGACAGCAGACUCAUCCUUGCACCCCUCCAUGGGCCUGGCCAAGCCCCCAAGAGGAUGGCAGCCUGGGCGUCGGAGCCACCUCCUGGGCAGCCAAUGAGGUGAGGGGCCGGAGGAGCAAGGGACAAGAGGAGCAGAGGACAGGUGAUGGAAAUCCUGCAGCUUUAGGCUCCAUUCUGCCAUCUACAUCCCAGCGCAGGGUGAAGCCUGAGAGCCCAAAUGGCCAACUCCACAGGGCUGAACGCCUCAGAAGUCGCAGGCUCGUUGGGGUUGAUCCUGGCAGCUGUCGUGGAGGUGGGGGCACUGCUGGGCAACGGCGCGCUGCUGGUCGUGGUGCUGCGCACGCCGGGACUGCGCGACGCGCUCUACCUGGCGCACCUGUGCGUCGUGGACCUGCUGGCGGCCGCCUCCAUCAUGCCGCUGGGCCUGCUGGCCGCACCGCCGCCCGGGCUGGGCCGCGUGCGCCUGGGCCCCGCGCCAUGCCGCGCCGCUCGCUUCCUCUCCGCCGCUCUGCUGCCGGCCUGCACGCUCGGGGUGGCCGCACUUGGCCUGGCACGCUACCGCCUCAUCGUGCACCCGCUGCGGCCAGGCUCGCGGCCGCCGCCUGUGCUCGUGCUCACCGCCGUGUGGGCCGCGGCGGGACUGCUGGGCGCGCUCUCCCUGCUCGGCACGCCGCCCGCACCGCCCCCUGCUCCUGCUCGCUGCUCGGUCCUGGCUGGGGGCCUCGGGCCCUUCCGGCCGCUCUGGGCCCUGCUGGCCUUCGCGCUGCCCGCCCUCCUGCUGCUCGGCGCCUACGGCGGCAUCUUCGUGGUGGCGCGUCGCGCUGCCCUGAGGCCCCCACGGCCGGCGCGCGGGUCCCGACUCCACUCGGACUCUCUGGAUAGCCGCCUUUCCAUCUUGCCGCCGCUCCGGCCUCGCCUGCCCGGGGGCAAGGCGGCCCUGGCCCCAGCGCUGGCCGUGGGCCAAUUUGCAGCCUGCUGGCUGCCUUAUGGCUGCGCGUGCCUGGCGCCCGCAGCGCGGGCCGCGGAAGCCGAAGCGGCUGUCACCUGGGUCGCCUACUCGGCCUUCGCGGCUCACCCCUUCCUGUACGGGCUGCUGCAGCGCCCCGUGCGCUUGGCACUGGGCCGCCUCUCUCGCCGUGCACUGCCUGGACCUGUGCGGGCCUGCACUCCGCAAGCCUGGCACCCGCGGGCACUCUUGCAAUGCCUCCAGAGACCCCCAGAGGGCCCUGCCGUAGGCCCUUCUGAGGCUCCAGAACAGACCCCCGAGUUGGCAGGAGGGCGGAGCCCCGCAUACCAGGGGCCACCUGAGAGUUCUCUCUCCUGAGCAGGAGAAAGGAGGGUGGUUUCCGUGGGGGCUCAUCCAACCCCUGCACAGGUCACAGCAGGUGCCCUGCUGGAUAUCUGGGUCUGGAACAGGAGGAGAAAGGGUGUCUGCUGCCUGGUGAGGCCCACGGACUUCUGAGAGCCAGGAAUCCUGCGGUCUGGGCCCAACACUGCAUAGCACUGUGCAUAGGCCGACCCUUCCUUAGGCCUCAGCUUUCCCAUCUGCACCCUGCAGCAUCUCUAAGGGCCCCUCCAGCAUAGGUGGUUUGUGAAACUCACAGGUGGUCCCCAGGCCAAGAUGGGCAGGUGUCACAAAGAAGAGGGCCCUAAGGGCUCACAACCAAAGUGAUCCGCCAAGCAGGGCAGUAUCUGGGUUACAGCCACAGCAGGAAGAACCACUGGAGAGACACUCAGAAGGACUUCCCUGACAUCUGCACCAAGGAGAGUCUGGACAAAGCUACUGAAACUCCUCCACCUGCUUCUAAAAUGCCCAGAAGACAACUGGACCAGUUUGGUAUUAGAAGUAGGAGGCUGGACGACUUCACCCCCAAAGGGUCCUGAAGCCCCAGAACUGGCAUGUGGAAGGGGCUGAGGCCUAAUUGAGGUUGGUGGAUUCACACAUGGGGGUCCUCCAGGACCUCAGCUGCACCCAUUUUCUGGAGGUUUUGCUGCCCACAACACCAGUAUUUCACAACUUCCUGGUCGCUGAGAAUAUUUAUUCAAAAACAGGGAUUGAAAAAA